ACUCGCCGUCAGAAGCACUCUGCUUGCUGUGCUCACCCCUCAGCUGUGGCCACCCUGGUGCCACUCCUUCCCUGGCCACCAUGUCACGGCAGCUCAACAUAGACGCGUUACGGCAGAACUUCUGGAAGGAGGAAUAUCUGAGGGAAAAGAUGUUGCGCUGUGAAUGGUACCGCAAGUAUGGGUCGAUGGUGAAGGCCAAGCAGAAGGCUAAGGCUGCAGCCCGCCUGCCCCUCAAACUGCCCACCCUGCACCCCAAAGCCCCACUCUCACCCCCACCCGCCCCCAAGUCAGCCCCUUCCAAGGUGCCCAGCCCUGUCCCAGAGGCGCCUUUUCAGUCGGAAAUGUACCCGGUACCACCUAUCACCCGAGCCCUGCUGUAUGAAGGCAUCUCCCACGACUUCCAGGGGCGGUACCGCUACCUCAACACUCGAAAACUGGACAUGCCAGAGACGCGAUACCUCUUCCCCAUCACCACCAGCUUCACGUAUGGCUGGCAGCUGGGCCCCCCAGUGAAGCAAGAACUGGUCUCCUGCAAGAUGUGCCGCAUUGAGUCAUUCUUCCGCAAGAACGGGGCCUUCGCACUGCUUGAUCCCCGAGACCUGGCCCUCUGACCGUGGGCCAGGUGUGGGCUUAGGGGAGGGAAGAAGAAAUAACAGGCCUCCUGGUGGGGCAAAGCUGCUGUGUGUGUCUGUGCCCCUCUGCUCUCCCUGUCCCUGAGGUUGCAUUCAGGCCUUUCUGAAACUAUCAGACCUGCAAGUUGCCCUCUUGCUUUUUCCGUAACCCUCAUCACUUUAAUCAUCCCUUUGAGGACUCAGCAAUGACCAGAGGGUGCUGGGAAGGGCGAGCACUACUUCGCAGGCACGGGAUCCUCAGCACCAGGGGAACACAGUAGUUCCAGGAAGUUCUGGGUGUUCCUGGGGAGAGAGCGGCUUGUCAUUUCGGAGGCCAGGGAAAGGGGCCUCCUGCCACCGCCACACCCCUCCUUGCCCGCCCCUCACCUGGCCCCGAGGGCCCGCAGCCGCUCCGUCCUCUCCCGAUGCAUUUGCUCCAGCUGCUCCCGCAGGGCGCGCCGCCGCCCAGCCGCGUCCUCCUGGCGGUGCGGAGCGCUGAGCGUCCGCGGCUCAGUGGGGCGGGCGGGGCAGCACCUGGCACACCUGCCCCUCGCGCCCCGCCGAGUCACUGCCAGAGUGCAGUGCGCUCACUUCAAAGGGACCCGGGCGCGCUAAGCUCGGCCCCUGCCCCGCGCAGGCUCCUUGUGGCCCCACCGCCUUCUAGGGGUCUUGCCUGUGGCGGGAGUUGAGCCGGACUGGGCGGGAGCCCCACGGGGUGAACCCGGCAGUGGCGGUUCCUGGCGAUGUGGAGGCGUUCCAGGACCUGCAGAGGCGGCAGUCAGCGUCCGGCCGCCCCUCGGUGCCCCGCCCGCUCCAGGCAGGCCCCGAUCCCGGCGUGGGGACACACCCGGAGCCGCUGCUGCUCACGGUCCCGCCGGCGGCGCUGCCGCCUGGCCGCGCUGUGCAGCUCCAGCAGCCGCUGCAGAGCCGUCACCUGCUGCGCCGCGCUUAAGCCCGCAGGCGCCUUGGCGGUGCUGAGGGGCGCCGGCCACGCGGCCUUCAAGGCCUUGGGACGCUCAGGGCCGCCCCACCCGACCCCGGAGGGCACCCGGAAGCCAAGCCUGGCCCACCUCCUGCUCCCCCGGUGCGGGGCCCACUCCAGGGCCCUGCAGCCCGUGCGGAUCGCGCUCCAGGCCUGGGGGCCCCGGAGAGCCCCGAGGAGCCCCUGCUGCCCGGAUACCUCGGCGCGCAGGGUCGCUGGCAUCUCGGCUCCGGCUCCGCGACCUGGGAGCCGCCGCCGGGCCGGGGGCUUCGGGCGGGUAAGCGCAGCCCACGCCCCCUCCCGGGCGGCCCCCAGCUUUGCCACCGCCGGUGCCGACCUUUGUGGCUCGCCUUUGAUCAUGCUCUGCGUCAGCGUGGUAGUCCUUCUCCGGAGGUUUGGGCUCUCCCUGCCCACAGGCUUUGGAGUCUGUGCUUUCAGGGACCCGCAGGAGUCCCUCGGAUGGCUAUGGGGGUCGCCUUCCUCUGGGGGCUGCACAGUGGCCUCUCCGGGAGCCACCUCCCAGGCUUGUGAGAUAUUGCCUUCCCAAGACCGCAGCAUCUUCUUCCCUGGACUCUGGGGACUCGCCUUUCCCUGGCACUUAGGACUAAAUUCUCUUCGACUCCUCCCUCUGACCCUGAGGAGCCCUUGGGCUCUGGCCCCCGUGUGUCUUCACCUUCUGACUCUGAGGAGCAUCUUUGAUCUCGCCCCAGGAGGCCUCGGCUCUCUUACGCUGAGGGGUCUCCGCUUUCUGAUCCUGAGGGUCCUCCUCUCAGACUCAGGGGUGUCCAUCCUUGGUGGUCUUUGAAGUUCUGCUCUCUCCUGGCCCAGGUGCGGGUCCGAGCCCAGCCCUUCAAGGGCAUCUUGGGAAGGCAGGUUUUGGGAGGGCAGGUCCCCCGGCCCAGGGGUCCCGGGAGUGAGCUUUCUUUUCUGGGUCUCAGGCUCUGCCUCACUCCUCUCUUCCCUCUGGGCCAGGUCCUGGAAAGGAAAAGCACUUUGGGCCCAGGUUUGAGAGGGAACCUGCAGACCCCAGGGGCCAGCCUUUGCCUGAUUCCUGAAUUUGUUAAAGCCAUUUUAUGUAGUGUGGAAGGUGCUUCACUGAAGAGCCUCCUCCUCACCCCAGCAGCCUCCUCCCAGGCAGACCCACCCCUGCCAUCCCCAACCUGAGACCCUUGACCUUUUCACCUUGCACUCUGAGCUACCUGGCACCCCAAAACUCCUCCUGGUAGUGGGGUUGAGCUCUUGUAAGGAGCCUGAGGAAGAAAGACCAGUAUUGGGAGCUCAUGUCCCAGCCCCUCAUGCACAGUUCACCUAGACUAGAGCCAGGAAGUUUAGGGAGUCCCAGUGCAUGGCUAGGGGUGCCCUGAGGGCGCUGUCUGAACCUCAGGCUGUCACAGUUCAUCAAUCAGCCAGCCAUGCACCUGUCAGGUGUGCCUGCCAACAGCCUGCCCCAUCUUUCUCAUCCUCCCAGCCAAGGCAGACCACUCCAGAGGGACCUGCACAGCCCCUUCCUCAAGACCACCACAGGAGGCCUGGGAGUGAGAAGGGUCACGGUGCUGGGUGCCUGGGUUCCUCAGCACCGGCCACUCCCACUUUGCCCUGGUGUGCCCAUCAGGCCCAGAGAAGAAACCCGCUCUGGGCGUCUUACUUUUUACUCUUAUUCAGAAAAACCUUCCUUAGCCUUUUCUUUGUUUCUGACAGCAAAAUCAAAGGAAAUUCAAGAUGAAAUUUUAGGCCAGAGCCUGGCCUAAAAACUGCAAGUGUUCAUAAUUAACAAAAGAAAUCUAAAAAAAGAGAUGAUGUGUUGCCGCUCCCCUGCAGCUGUGGAGGAAGGAGAGCUGUUCUGCAUCCAUAAAAACCAGUUAAAAGGGAUUUCAUAAGGUCUGAAAUUGAGAACUUUCCCAAGAAUACUGCAUCUUGUUCUCUUGUGCAAUAUACAGACGUGUGAAUAUUCCUAACAGUAACCAAAUGGGUGCACUCUCUGUGAAAACGCAUCUUUCAAAGAGUUUUUUAAACAAAGGAGACUCCUGGGCCUUUAGAAAUAAUUGCCACAAACUGCAAAAACAAUCUCCAACCUCCCACUUCUGUAAUUCUCAUCUGUUGUCUUACUAGAAAAUUUAUUUCUCUGGUAAUAAUGUUAUAAUUGAUAUCCCUGUCUUCUCAAGAUGUAAAAUACUUGUAAAAACUUCUCUGUCCAUCAGAAAAUAAUUAUUGGCACUUUUCUUCUCUCUCAUGUGCAUGAUGGAACAAUAAAAAGCUUAUGGCUUUGCUAGAUCUAUUAUUUAACAAACAA